AGUUUGUAAUCUGACACAGUACACUGCAGUUGUCUCCGAGGUGAACCUCCGGAGCCUUGGCACAGCUCGCUUCUAAAGCUUGGAAAUGACCCGCCACACCUGAAGCCUGCAGGUGCUGAGGCCACAUUCGAUCAGACCCAAGCUUUGGGAGACCGCUGGGGAAAUUUCCCACUUCCUCUCCUGAGACCAGGAACUCAGCAGAGAAACUUUGUGGAAAAUGAACUGAAGGAUGCCACCCAGGGAGAGUAUCUCCUGAGAUCCCAUCAUGCAGGCCUUCCCACAAGGGCCCGGCAGCAUGACAAGGUGAAGGCAGAGUAUGUGCAUCUCAACCAUCCGCUCACCCUCGUGACCAGAGAGCGCGAUUUGGCCGUGAAGGAGAAACACCAGCUCCAAGCCAAGCUGGAGAACCUAGAACAGGUCCUGAAGCAUAUGCGAGAGGCGGCUGAACGGCGGCAGCAGCUGCAGUUGGAGCAUGACCAGGCCCUGGCUGUUCUCAGUGCCAAGCAGCAGGAAAUUGACCUUCUGCAGAAGGCUCAGGUUGAGGCUAAGAAGGAGCAUGAAGGCGCAGUGCGGCUGCUAGAGUCCAAGGUUCGAGAGCUGGAAGAGAAAUGCCGGACUCAAAGUGAGCAGUUCAACCUGCUGUCCCGGGACCUGGAGAAGUUCCGGCAGCACGCUGGCAAGAUUGACCUGCUGGGUGGCAGCGCGGUGGCCCCCCUGGACAUCUCCACGGCCCCCAGCAAGCCUUUCCCACAGUUCAUGAAUGGCCUAGCCACCUCCCUCGGCAAAGGUCAGGAGAGCGCUAUUGGAGGCAGCUCUGCGAUCGGUGAAUAUAUCCGGCCCCUUCCGCAGCCUGGUGACAGGCCGGAGCCUCUGUCCGCCAAGCCCACCUUCCUGUCGAGAUCCGGUAGCGCAAGAUGCAGAUCUGAGUCAGACAUGGAGAAUGAACGGAAUUCCAAUACCUCCAAGCAGAGAUACUCGGGGAAGGUCCACCUCUGUGUUGCCCGCUAUAGUUACAACCCCUUCGAUGGACCGAACGAGAACCCCGAAGCUGAGCUGCCCCUCACGGCGGGAAAAUACCUCUACGUCUAUGGAGACAUGGAUGAGGAUGGGUUCUAUGAAGGAGAGCUCCUCGAUGGCCAGAGGGGUCUGGUGCCCUCCAACUUCGUGGACUUUGUGCAGGACAACGAGUCGCGGUUGGCAAGCACGCUGGGGAACGAGCAGGAUCAGAACUUCAUCAACCAUUCCGGCAUCGGCCUGGAGGGAGAGCACAUCCUGGACCUCCACUCCCCAACCCACAUAGAUGCGGGCAUCACCGACAACAGUGCCGGGACCCUGGACGUGAACAUCGACGACAUCGGAGAAGACAUCGUGCCUUACCCUAGAAAAAUCACCCUCAUCAAACAACUCGCCAAAAGUGUUAUUGUGGGCUGGGAGCCCCCGGCGGUGCCACCAGGAUGGGGAACGGUGAGCAGCUACAACGUCCUGGUGGACAAGGAGACACGCAUGAACCUCACGCUGGGGAGCAGAACUAAAGCCCUCAUCGAGAAGCUCAACAUGGCAGCCUGCACCUACCGCAUCUCCGUGCAGUGCGUCACCAGCAGGGGCAGCUCGGAUGAGCUGCAGUGCACGCUGCUGGUGGGCAAGGACGUGGUGGUGGCCCCCUCCCACCUGCGGGUGGACAACAUCACGCAGAUCUCCGCCCAGCUCUCCUGGCUACCCACCAACAGCAACUACAGCCACGUCAUCUUCCUCAACGAGGAGGAGUUCGACAUCGUCAAGGCCGCCAGGUACAAGUACCAGUUCUUCAAUCUCAGGCCCAACAUGGCCUAUAAGGUGAAGGUUCUGGCCAAACCCCACCAGAUGCCGUGGCAGCUCCCGCUGGAGCAAAGGGAGAAGAAGGAGGCCUUUGUGGAGUUCUCCACGUUGCCUGCAGGACCCCCAGCACCCCCACAAGAUGUUACCGUCCAGGCUGGGGUGACCCCCGCCACCAUCCGGGUCUCCUGGAGACCACCUGUGCUGACGCCCACCGGGCUGUCCAAUGGCGCAAACGUUACCGGCUACGGCGUGUAUGCCAAAGGGCAGAGGGUGGCUGAAGUCAUCUUCCCCACGGCAGACAGCACGGCCGUGGAGCUUGUGCGGCUGCGGAGCCUGGAGGCCAAGGGCGUGACCGUGCGGACCCUCUCCGCCCAGGGCGAGUCCGUGGACUCUGCAGUUGCUGCCGUUCCCCCCGAGCUCCUGGUGCCUCCUACCCCCCACCCGAGACCUGCACCCCAAUCAAAGCCAUUAGCAAGUUCUGGAGUCCCCGAAACCAAAGACGAGCACCUGGGUCCCCACGCCAGGAUGGAUGAGGCCUGGGAGCAGAGCCGUGCACCUGGCCCUGUGCAUGGGCACAUGCUGGAGCCGCCCGUGGGCCCCGGAAGGCGGUCGCCCUCACCCAGCCGCAUCCUGCCACAGCCACAGGGCACCCCGGUGUCCACCACCGUCGCCAAGGCCAUGGCCCGGGAGGCCGCGCAGAGGGUGGCCGAGAGCAGCAGGUUAGAGAAAAGGAGCGUCUUCCUAGAGAGAAGCAGCGCGGGGCAGUACGCCGCCUCAGACGAGGAGGACGCCUAUGACUCUCCAGACUUCAAGAGGAGGGGCGCCUCGGUGGACGACUUCCUGAAAGGCUCUGAACUUGGCAAGCAGCCGCACUGUUGCCAUGGAGACGAGUACCACACAGAGAGCAGCCGGGGGUCUGACCUCUCAGACAUCAUGGAGGAGGACGAGGAGGAGCUGUAUUCUGAAAUGCAGCUGGAAGAUGGGGGAAGGAGGCGGCCCAGCGGCACGUCCCACAAUGCCCUCAAGGACUGCACUGACCAUAGGACCUCGGAAGGCACUUUCUGGGAGCAGCCCGAGUUUCCCCACCAGCCCCACAGGAAGAGACUUUUCAGUAUCCCCGAAGUAGCGGAAGAGGACGGAGAGUGCUGUGGGCUGCUACACAAGCAGGGUGCAGGGCCGUCCCCCAGGGCCAGGACGGGGCUGGCCAGAGAGCCCAGGCCCGGCAGGCCCUACAGGGGCGACGAGGCCCCUCGGGGCUCCUGGUUCCCGGUGAAGCACAGGGGCUCGGGGGCCGUCCCCCACGUGGAGGACUUCCUUCUGGAAGACAGGGGCUGUCGGUUCAGCCGCUCGGCCACCCGGAGCCCGGACAGCGGCCUGGACUGUGGGAGUGAAGAGGACGAGUCGCGGUUUGGCUUCGGAAACACCGUGGCCGCGUGCAGCCCAGGCCCUGGUCACUGUCCCUGCAGGAGGGGCCCGAGGCCGCUGCUGGCCCGGCGGCGGACGCUGACCCGGCAGAGCAGCGUGGAGGAGGACUUUGGGGAGCAGGUGGGCCCUGGUGGCCUCCUCAGGAACGACGACCCCCAGCCCGGCCCGGAGAGGCCGCCCCCCAGGAAGCACGGCUGGGGCGAGCCCACCGAGCACCAAGAUUUUCGGGGUGUCUGGAAGAAAAGCAUAACCAUGCCCGACAGUAGGGCAGCUGCCCCCCACGCAAAGCCACCUCCCAGAGUCGCACAAGGCCCCCUGAUUUUAGGGAACCCAGCCUCUGCAGGACGGGUGGAUCACAUGGGCCGGAGGUUUCCCCGUGGCAGCGCUGGUCCUCAGAGGUCCCGGCCCGUGACAGUCCCAUCCAUCGACGAUUACGGGCGAGACCGCCUUUCUCCAGACUUCUAUGAAGAGUCAGAAACUGACCCUGGUGCCGAAGAGCUCCCGGCCCGGAUCUUUGUGGCUCUCUUUGACUACGACCCGCUCACCAUGUCCCCAAACCCAGAUGCUGCAGAGGAGGAGCUUCCCUUUAAAGAAGGCCAGAUCAUCAAGGUUUAUGGUGAUAAAGACGCUGAUGGAUUCUACCGUGGGGAAACCUGUGCCCGGCUUGGCCUUAUUCCUUGUAACAUGGUCUCUGAGAUACAAGCAGAUGAUGAGGAGAUGAUGGAUCAGCUUCUUAGACAGGGCUUUCUCCCUCUGAAUACACCUGUGGAGAAAAUAGAGAGAAGCAGGAGAAGUGGCAGGCGUCAUUCGGUAUCGACGCGGAGAAUGGUGGCCCUGUAUGACUACGACCCCAGAGAAAGCUCGCCCAACGUCGAUGUCGAGGCCGAACUUACAUUUUGCACAGGAGAUAUUAUUACAGUUUUUGGUGAAAUUGAUGAAGAUGGAUUUUAUUAUGGGGAGCUGAAUGGGCAGAAAGGCCUUGUGCCCUCAAACUUCUUGGAAGAAGUGCCUGAUGACGUAGAAGUCUAUCUUUCUGAUGCUCCAUCCCACUACUCUCAAGAUACGCCAAUGCGCUCAAAGGCAAAAAGGGUAAGCAAACCUAUUUAGCCUUUUUAAUCUCUGUCCCGUUCUGCCAUAUGUGGUCUAAUACAAUCUUUGCACUGAUAUUUUUAUAUCUUGGGCCGAAAAGCGUAAAUACACCCUGAAUUUUUUUUCUCUGCCCUGAAGCCAUGGGAGUUGUACCUAAAAAUUCUUAAUUCUAAAUCUUACUCAUUUUACAAAAAAAGACCCUUUCAAUUCUAAUCAAUCAAUCUGCCUUUACUCACAAAGAAAUGUCCCAUCCUACAUUAUAGAAGCACAUUUCAGUUUGAUCAAGAGUGAAAAGGGGAUGGCUCCUCUUCAGAUUUGGUGGGCAAUGGAGGUUAUUUGCCCUCUGUUAGGACUUUAGUCUCUUCACAAGGAUCCAAGGGCUUCUCAAGCAUAUUGAACUAUUAGACUACAUUCAUGUUUAGUAUCUCAUUUUUAUUUUAUUUCAUCACUGCAAGUUUUUCUAUAUUAUAUUUUUAUAUAUAUAUUUUUAUUUCUUUGCUCAUCUGCUUGGAAACAGAAGAAGAGUGUUCAUUUCACACCUUAAUCAGGCAAUGUAGCCUUCACGUAAGUGAGCAACUGAAGAUACCGAUAAAGAUACCAACUUAAGCUACCUUAACCGGGCCAGUGUGGUAGACUUAAGGCUUCAUUGUGGGGUUAAAAAAAAAAAAAGAUACAAAGAAAUAUGUCUCAAAAAACUAUUGGACCUAAAUAAUUAGAAUAUUACUUGGUCUCAGUUGUAAAGCAACUGAAUUUAUAGUGAAGCAAAUCAUCUUUAAUAAUCAUUUCCUACUAUUUGCAUUAAGAAUAUUUGAAAGGCCAACAUUGGGAACAUAUUUCUUAACAAGCUAACUGUGUGUUUACAUAGAGAGAGCUGCAUAUUGCAUUGUUAGCCACUCUUGGAAAAAGCACAACCUAACAAACAUGUUUACUAUAGGAAGCUUUACUUUAGAAACUUAACCCAAGGUCAAGCAGAUGAGUAGUGAACACAGGUGAUCGAGUGUUGGCUCUGAACACUCCAAACACUGGCUCGAGUGGCCAGAACGUGUUUUCCUUAAGUAACCCUGCCUCUACCUUACGAGAGAGCUAUGCUCCUCCUCAAAGCACAAUCAUCCUGUGACAGAAGUUGCUGCAACACGCGUUUGUUGUUGGUAUACCAAUGCAAUACUAAGUUGAUGAAGCACGCAGCUCAAAUGAUCACAUUAGAUGGAAUAGAUGGUAUCUUCAGGUGUACUUUGGGAUGCUUUACUAGGUGUUUUCCAUUAGAAUUAGACCUUGAUUUUAAAUCCAAGCAAGCUUGAAGCCCCUUGGCUUACAGCAUUUGCCUGCUGAAUACUAAACACUCACAUGGCAAGAGUUGCUCUGGAGAGGUAGGGCCAGAGGAAUGCUGCUGCACUGCCAACUCAGGCACAUGCUUAGCUGUAAAGGGAAGCGAGGUGAAGUCGUCCUGCAGCGUAUUAGAGUAAAAGUCUACCCCUCUGAAGCACUAUUAAGCGCUUAACGUAUAUUUAAAUACUACCAUGUGCUAUCUACUGAGGAAGAUUCAUGUUCAAUUAUUUGGAAAUAAUGCAAGCAUCCACUAAGGGCCUUUAAGCUUUCUUUGAUUAUAAUUAAGGUUCAUUUUAGUUUUUUUUUUUCUUUCAACCAGUGUGCCAUCUCCAAUAUUUCUAUAGUAUACCAACCACCCCAGGAAUGCACUUUAACAAUAUCAGGAUUUUAUAUAACCAAAUAGUUUCAAAUACAACAAAAUUCCCUUUAUGAACUUUCGCUUUUUAAGACUACUGAUGGGUACUCGGCCAACUUUACUAUCAACCUAAUUUCAGAUCAUGUCUCCCCUGCCCUUAGUCUUCAUUUAUGAAGUGAAUUAUUACCUGCCUUAGCUUUGCCAAAGCAACGGCCACCCCGCACUCCCUCGAGACAGAGAAACGGAACCCACACAUUUAUGUCUGGGGCCUCUCUCUGGCGUGCUGUGGGAGAGGACCUUUGCUUCUCAUGGCAUACUUCAACAACUGAAAGAACAAAUGAACCCCCCUGACCUUUCCUGGUGGGAAACGGGGACAGUACGAUGUUACCAAGUGAAUUCUGUUGUUGGCGCUCACACACUCAAUAAACUGUAACACUGUACCUACUAGGUUCCUCCUGAGGGUUCAGGUACAGCAAGGAGAGCUCCAUCCCCCACAGUCCAUCUCCAUUCGGGGUCACCUACGUCAUCUAUGGGUUCUGGUAGUCCUGGGAGAGGCAGGGAAAUGUCCUCGAAAAAGAAAAAGGGGCUGCUUUCCAAAGGCAAGAAACUGCUGAAAAAGCUGGGUGCAGUGAAAUGAUUCAUGUGCUUCCGGACAACUGCCAAAUCUAUGUAAUUUUCUUUAAUUCCAAACUAGGGCUUUCAUGACUCAAGUACUUCCUAAAAAAACCCAAUCUUCUCCCCUGACACCAGUAGAGAAAUGCACUUUUGCACUACCAACCACUUUAAACCAACCACGAGAACAAAGAGGAGCGGUUGCUCUCUGUCACCGCUGGCAGUCUGCUCUCAUUGUCCAAGCUCUGAUUUGGGAGGUGGGAGGGGACGUCUUAUUAACAAACGGGGGCGCAUAGCUAUCACCUGUAGCUCCCUCCCUACCUGUAAUUCCAGUCUUUGUGCAUUUGUCAUCUGCCCUUAAAGGAAUGAUUUUCAACCUUUCUCCCUUCUCAAAAUGCUUGCCUCAUAAUGCAUAACUUUCACUUUGACUCUGGUCUUGAAAUUCCUAGUUUAAUUCGCCUUGAUGUUCUGCCUUAUAAAUGCACAAUGAUUUGUACUGUCUAAUAAAAACAGUGUAUACUUUGUAUGUGUCGUGCAUUCAGUGGUCUUCAUCCUGACACAGUGGUUUGAGAUCAAGUUGUACAGGCUGUGCAUUUUAAGAUACUAGUUUCAGUCUUUCAAAGCCAGCCAGGCUACACACAGAAAAUGUUUACUCAAUCAUUCAAAAAAGAGAAAAGGAGAGAAAGUAACUUUGUUUGGUAAAGCACCAGUACUCCAACCUUCCAGAAAGCCGAUUAUCUUCAUUGCUUUUAAUGUUCUAUUCUGUGGCAUAUGGUUUUCUGUUACUUUCGUUGUCAAAAUGCCAUACCCAAAUACACAGCAAUGAAUGGCACACAAGUAAUCCACAUAAUGCAUAAGCCACACCAAAACCAGACUCAAUUUAAAUCUGCUCCAAAUGAGUCCAUACCCAUCUUCAUCAUUGGCAUUUGAACAAAAGACUUACUUACAAAGUUGCUGGCAGAUGUAUUUGAUGGUUACUCUUUUGUAAUUCUUGUCCACUUGUAAAUUGUUUUUACUCUUUAUACAUACUUUUCAGACUGCCUUUCUUUUGUAAUUUAUGGACGGUUUAUAAAUGAAUGACAAAGCUUUCCCCAUUGUGUCUUCAAAAACGCUAUUAUAAAUUGUAAUAUAAUAGUAUGUGGUAGAUUUAUUAUUAAAGGAAAUCCAUGUGUGGUUAAGCUCUGUGUGGGUGUGUGCAUGUGCACAGUUAGUGUAAAAUAUUUUCUAGAAAUAAAAUUUGUUAUUUUAUACAA